GAGUUCCUGGAAGGCUGGUUUGAAGGCGGUGCCGGGGUGGGGGUGAGGCUCAGCAGAGCCCGGGGCACAGGCCGGAGGGGCUGCAGGCGCGAGGCUGGGUUACGUGAGGAAGCUGGGGGUUUCGCGGGCAGCUUUAGAGCCCCAGUCAGGGAAACCGAGGCCGGGCUUCCUGGCUGCCUCGCGAGCCUCUUCAUGGCUCUCGCCGCCGCCCUGAGGUGCCUAGAAUGGGUUCCGGCCUCCGGGGAGGUUCCCAGUAACCGCAGGAGCCACCAUUGAUUUGGCGUCUGCUGGGUGCAAAGCCCAGCGCGCUAACCCUUUACUCGCGACCUUUCGCUUCACCUUCACAGCAGCCCUGCGAGGAGAGUUGUGGACUGGGGCAACCUUUGCCAGUGAUGAGAAGUGAUGCUCGUGGCAGUGCUGAAUCUCUCUGAAUAUGAUUCGAAUUGCAGCCUUAAAUGCCAGCUCCACCAUUGAGGAUGAUCAUGAAGGAAGCUUUAAAAGUCACAAAACCCAGACAAAGGAGGCUCAGGAAGCAGAGGCUUUUGCAUUGUACCACAAGGCCCUUGAUCUGCAGAAACAUGACCGGUUUGAGGAGUCUGCCAAAGCCUACCAUGAGCUCUUGGAGGCGAGCCUGCUGCGGGAGGCAGUUUCAUCCGGUGAUGAGAAAGAGGGGUUGAAACACCCUGGGCUGAUACUGAAAUAUUCCACUUAUAAGAACUUGGCCCAGCUGGCAGCCCAGCGGGAGGAUCUGGAGACAGCCAUGGAGUUCUACUUAGAGGCAGUGAUGCUGGACUCCACAGAUGUCAACCUCUGGUAUAAGAUUGGACAUGUGGCCCUGAGGCUCAUCCGGAUCCCCCUGGCUCGCCAUGCUUUUGAGGAAGGGCUGCGGUGCAAUCCUGACCACUGGCCCUGUUUGGAUAACCUAAUCACUGUCCUGUACACCCUCAGUGAUUACACAACAUGUCUGUACUUCAUCUGCAAAGCUUUGGAGAAGGAUUGCCGGUACAGCAAAGGGCUGGUCCUCAAGGAGAAGAUUUUUGAGGAGCAGCCUUGUCUCCGGAAGGACUCUCUCAGAAUGUUCCUCAAAUGUGACAUGUCGAUUCACGAUGUUUCGGUGAGUGCAGCUGAGACACAGGCGAUUGUAGAUGAGGCCUUGGGGCUGCGAAAAAAGAGGCAAGCGCUGAUUGUGCGGGAGAAGGAGCCGGACCUGAAACUUGUGCAGCCCAUUCCUUUCUUCACCUGGAAGUGCCUCGGAGAGAGCUUGCUGGCCAUGUACAAUCAUCUCACCACCUGUGAGCCCCCACGUCCCAGCCUUGGCAAAAGGAUUGAUUUGUCGGACUACCAGGACCCCAGCCAGCCUCUUGAGUCCUCCAUGGUGGUGACGCCAGUUAACGUGAUCCAGCCAAGCACUGUCAGCACCAACCCAGCUGUGGCUGUCGCCGAGCCUGUGGUCUCCUACACCUCUGUGGCUACAACCAGCUUCCCACUGCACAGUCCUGGUCUGUUGGAGACAGGCGCUCCUGUGGGUGAUAUUUCUGGGGGAGAUAAAUCCAAGAAAGGGGUAAAACGGAAGAAGAUUUCAGAAGAGAGUGGAGAAACAGCAAAGCGGCGGUCUGCCCGUGUCCGAAACACCAAGUGCAAAAAAGAAGAGAAAGUAGACUUCCAGGAGCUUCUGAUGAAGUUCUUGCCGUCCAGGUUAAGAAAGCUGGACCCUGAGGAGGAAGAUGAUUCCUUUAAUAACUAUGAAGUCCAGUCAGAAGCCAAACUGGAAAGCUUCCCAAGCAUUGGGCCUCAAAGGCUGUCAUUUGACUCAGCCACAUUCAUGGAAUCUGAAAAGCAGGACGUGCAUGAGUUCCUGCUGGAGAACCUAACCAACGGGGGCAUCCUGGAGCUGAUGAUGCGCUACCUGAAAGCCAUGGGCCACAAGUUCUUGGUAAGGUGGCCUCCAGGCUUGGCGGAGGUCGUGCUCAGCGUCUACCACAGCUGGAGGAGGCACAGCACCAGCCUGCCCAACCCGCUGCUGAGGGACUGCAGCAACAAGCACAUCAAGGACAUGAUGCUGAUGUCUCUCUCCUGCAUGGAACUCCAGCUGGACCAGUGGCUGCUGACCAAAGGCAGAAGCUCUGCAGUGUCUCCUCGGAACUGCCCUGCUGGUAUGGUGAAUGGCAGAUUUGGACCUGACUUCCCAGGGACCCACUGCCUGGGUGACCUCCUACAGCUGUCAUUUGCCUCGUCCCAGCGCGACCUGUUCGAGGAUGGUUGGCUGGAGUUUGUGGUCCGUGUUUACUGGCUGAAGGCUCGCUUCCUGGCGCUGCAGGGAGACAUGGAGCAGGCCCUGGAGAACUAUGACAUCUGCACAGAAAUGCUCCAGAGUUCCACCGCCAUCCAGGUGGAGGCAGGGGCUGAACGAAGAGACAUUGUCAUCCGGCUGCCCAACCUCCAUAAUGACUCUGUGGUUUCCCUGGAGGAGAUUGAUAAGAACCUGAAGUCGCUGGAGCGGUGCCAGUCCCUGGAGGAGAUUCAGCGGCUGUAUGAAGCAGGCGACUACAAGGCUGUUGUGCAUCUGCUCCGCCCCACUUUGUGCACCAGUGGGUUUGACCGGGCCAAACACCUGGAGUUUAUGACUUCCAUUCCUGAGAGGCCAGCCCAGCUGCUUCUUCUGCAGGACUCCUUGCUCCGGCUGAAGGACUAUCGGCAGUGUUUUGAGUGUUCCGAUGUGGCUCUGAACGAGGCUGUCCAGCAGAUGGUGAACUCAGGUGAGGCUGCCGCCAAGGAGGAGUGGGUGGCCACAGUGACCCAACUGCUGAUGGGCAUCGAGCAGGCCCUCUCUGCGGACAGCAGUGGUAGCAUCCUGAAGGUAUCAUCCUCCACCACUGGCCUUGUGCGGCUCACCAACAACCUCAUCCAGGUCAUUGACUGCAGCAUGGCUGUGCAGGAGGAGGCCAAGGAGCCCCACGUCUCUUCAGUGCUACCCUGGAUCAUUCUACACCGGAUCAUCUGGCAGGAGGAAGACACCUUCCAUUCUCUGUGCCACCAGCAGCAGCUCCAAAACCCAGCGGAGGAAGGGAUGUCAGAGACGCCCAUGCUCCCAUCCUCCCUCAUGCUGCUGAACACAGCCCACGAGUAUUUGGGCAGAAGGUCCUGGUGCUGCAAUUCAGAUGGGGCUCUGCUGCGAUUCUAUGUGCGAGUACUCCAGAAGGAACUGGCUGCAUCCACCUCUGAAGACACGCACCCUUACAAGGAGGAGCUGGAGACAGCCUUGGAGCAGUGCUUCUACUGCCUGUACAGCUUCCCCAGCAAGAAGAGUAAGGCCAGGUACCUGGAGGAACACUCGGCCCAGCAGGUGGAUCUUAUAUGGGAGGAUGCACUGUUCAUGUUUGAGUAUUUUAAGCCCAAGACCCUUCCUGAAUUUGACAGCUAUAAGACCAGCACCGUGUCUGCUGACUUGGCCAACCUACUGAAGAGAAUUGCCACCAUUGUGCCUCGCACAGAGAGGCCAGCCCUUAGCCUGGACAAAGUCUCUGCCUACAUUGAGGGAACUUCAACUGAGGUACCCUGCCUCCCAGAGGGGGCUGACCCCUCCCCUCCAGUGGUGAACGAGCUUUACUACCUCCUGGCUGAUUAUCAUUUCAAAAACAAGGAGCAGUCCAAGGCCAUCAAGUUCUACAUGCAUGACAUCUGCAUCUGCCCCAAUAGGUUUGAUUCCUGGGCAGGCAUGGCUCUGGCCCGGGCCAGCCGCAUUCAGGACAAGCUGAACUCCAAUGAGCUGAAGAGUGAUGGGCCCAUUUGGAAGCAUGCCACGCCCGUCUUGAACUGCUUCCGUCGGGCCCUGGAGAUUGACAGCUCCAACUUGUCCCUAUGGAUUGAGUAUGGCACCAUGUCCUAUGCCUUGCACUCAUUCGCCUCACGUCAAUUGAAGCAGUGGAGAGGCGAGCUGCCCCCUGAGCUCGUGCAGCAGAUGGAGGGCCGGCGCGACAGCAUGCUAGAGACAGCCAAGCACUGUUUCACAUCAGCAGCCCGCUGCGAGGGUGAUGGUGACGAGGAGGAGUGGCUCAUCCACUACAUGCUGGGCAAGGUGGCUGAGAAGCAGCAGCAGCCACCCACCGUUUACUUGCUGCACUACAGGCAGGCUGGCCACUACCUGCACGAGGAGGCUGCCCGCUACCCCAAGAAGAUCCACUACCACAACCCACCUGAGCUGGCCAUGGAGGCCCUGGAGGUGUACUUUCGGCUCCAUGCUUCCAUCCUGAAGCUCCUGGGGAAGCCCGAUUCUGGGGUUGGUGCAGAGGUCCUGGUCAACUUUAUGAAGGAGGCUGCAGAAGGACCCUUUGCCAGGGGCGAGGAGAAGAACACACCCAAAGCUUCAGAAAAGGAGAAGGCCUGCCUGGUGGACGAGGACUCCCACUCUUCAGCUGGGACACUGCCGGGCCCCGGAGCCUCCCUCCCCUCCUCCUCUGGCCCAGGUCUGACAUCCCCACCUUACACAGCCACUCCGAUUGACCACGAUUACGUCAAAUGUAAAAAACCCCACCAGCAGGCAACGCCGGACGGUACAGUCCCUGUUCUCCCUACUGCCAGCCCAGGGCGGCACAUCAAUCACGGGGGGGUGCUCGGACGACUCAUUUUGUCGCUUCGUUUUGACCGAAGCCAGGACAGCACAGCCGUAGCACUCUCAGACUCUAGCUCAACGCAGGACUUCUUUAAUGAGCCCACCAGCUUACUGGAAGGCUCCAGGAAAUCCUACACAGAGAAGAGGCUGCCCAUUCUCAGUUCCCAAGCAGGAGCGACGGGUAAAGAUCUUCAGGGGGCCACAGAAGAAAGAGGAAAAAACGAGGAGUCAUUGGAGAGUACAGAAGGCUUCCGGGCUGCAGAGCAAGGUGUCCAGAAGCCUGCUGCAGAAACCCCAGCCUCUGCUUGCAUCCCUGGCAAGCCCUCAGCAUCCACACCCACCCUGUGGGAUGGGAAGAAGAGAGGGGACCUCCCAGGGGAGCCAGUGGCCUUCCCCCAGGGGCUGCCGGCUGGUGCUGAGGAGCAGCGGCAGUUUCUCACAGAGCAGUGCAUCGCCUCCUUCCGCCUGUGCCUGAGCCGCUUCCCCCAGCACUAUAAGAGUCUCUACCGUCUGGCCUUCCUCUACACCUACAGCAAGACCCACCGGAACCUCCAGUGGGCCCGCGACGUGUUGCUAGGCAGCAGUAUCCCGUGGCAACAACUGCAGCACAUGCCGGCACAGGGGCUCUUCUGCGAGAGGAACAAGACCAAUUUCUUCAACGGCAUCUGGCGGAUCCCCGUGGACGAGAUUGACCGGCCGGGCAGCUUUGCCUGGCACAUGAACCGCUCCAUCGUGCUGCUGCUCAAGGUGCUGGCCCAGCUGCGGGACCACAGCACCCUGCUGAAGGUGUCCUCCAUGCUUCAGCGGACCCCAGACCAGGGCAAGAAGUAUCUGCGAGAUGCUGACCGCCAGGUCCUGGCGCAGCGGGCCUUCAUCCUCACUGUGAAGGUGCUCGAAGACACGCUGAGCGAGCUCGCAGAGGGGUCAGAACGCCCAGGGCCCAAGGUCUGUGGCCUCCCCGGAGCCAGGAUGACCACCGAUGUCUCACACAAGGCCAGUCCUGAGGAUGGCCAGGAGGGCCUCCCCCAGCCGAAGAAGCCCCCUCUGGCUGAUGGCUCAGGGCCAGGGCCCGAGCCAGGAGGCAAAGUGGGCCUCCUCAACCACCGGCCUGUGGCCAUGGAUGCAGGAGACAGUGCAGACCAAAGCGGGGAGCGGAAGGAUAAAGAGAGCCCACGGGCAGGGCCCACUGAGCCCAUGGACACGAGUGAGGCCACUGUUUGCCACUCAGACUUGGAGCGGACACCACCCCUGCUGCCAGGUCGCCCCGCAAGGGACCGGGGCCCCGAGAGCCGGCCCACUGAGCUGUCCCUGGAGGAGCUGAGCAUCAGUGCCCGGCAGCAGCCCACCCCGCUCACCCCAGCCCAGCCAGCCCCCGCCCCCGCCCCCGCCACCACCACAGGGACCAGGGCAGGGGGCCACCCGGAGGAGCCGCUCUCCCGGCUCAGCCGCAAGAGGAAGCUCCUGGAGGACACAGAGUCAGGCAAGACACUUCUGUUGGAUGCCUACCGUGUGUGGCAGCAGGGCCAGAAGGGUGUGGCCUAUGACCUGGGCCGUGUGGAGAGGAUCAUGUCGGAGACCUACAUGCUCAUCAAGCAGCAUCUCCCUGUUAAGGUGGAUGAGGAGGCUGCGCUGGAGCAGGCUGUGAAGUUCUGCCAGGUCCAUCUUGGGGCUGCCGCCCAGAGACAGGCCUCGGGGGACACCCCCACCACUCCAAAGCACCCCAAAGACAGCCGAGAGAACUUCUUUCCUGUGACAGUGGUGCCCACAGCCCCUGACCCUGUGCCAGCUGACUCUGUCCAGCGGCCCAGUGAUGCUCACACCAAGCCUCGCCCUGCACUAGCUGCCGCCACAACUAUUAUCACCUGCCCUCCGUCAGCAUCAGCUUCCACCCUGGACCAGUCCAAGGACCCUGGGCCUCCCCGGCCACACAGGCCUGAAGCUACCCCCAGCAUGGCCUCUCUGGGCCCAGAGGGAGAAGAGCUGGCGAGAGUGGCAGAGGGCACCAGCUUCCCGCCUCAGGAGCCACGGCACAGUCCGCAGGUGAAGAUGGCCCCCACAAGUUCCCCGGCAGAGCCACACUGCUGGCCGGCAGAGGCUGCCCUGGGCACAGGCGCUGAGCCCACCUGCAGCCAGGAGGGGAAACUGAGGCCUGAGCCGAGAAGGGAUGGGGAGGCUCAGGAGGCUGCGAGUGAGACUCAGCCCCUGAGCUCUCCCCCAACAGCUGCCAGCUCCAAGGCCCCCAGCAGUGGGAGUGCCCAGCCACCAGAGGGUCACCCAGGCAAGCCUGAGCCCAGCCGGGCUAAGUCCCGCCCCCUGCCCAACAUGCCAAAGCUGGUCAUCCCCUCCGCCGCCACCAAGUUCCCCCCUGAGAUCACCGUCACGCCACCCACCCCAACCCUGCUCUCCCCCAAAGGCAGCAUCUCGGAGGAGACCAAGCAGAAGCUGAAGUCAGCCAUCCUUUCUGCCCAGUCUGCUGCCAACGUGAGGAAGGAGAGCCUAUGCCAGCCAGCCCUGGAGGUCCUGGAGACAUCCAGCCAGGAGUCCUCGCUGGAGAGCGAGACAGACGAGGACGACGACUACAUGGACAUUUGAGGGGCCACUGCAGCCCCACCGCCACGCCCCAGGGGACCAGCCAGGCCUGGAAUGCCCCCUGGGCAGGACCCUGGGCAGGACCAGAGGCCCACAUGGAUGCCACUCCCCACACAGCCCCCAGGCCUGCCCAGCCCACCUCCUCAUGGCAUCCUCCCUGUACCCAGGUCAGGCUGUCCACACCACAUGGGAGCCCAGAGGAGGAGGGGCCCGCCUUAGCCAUGUGAAGGUGGAUUGGUCGCCAUCUGCACGCCAGGCGGCAUCCUUUUCUAUGAAGUGUUGACUUUGUAAAUCUGCCCACACCCAGCUGGCCAUAUCCACCCCUCGACGCCGGGAUGAGCCGGCUCUGCCUGUGUCACAGUGGAGGGGUCCUUUAGGGCCAGGCUCACCCCUCACCCUUUUUUUGGUUGCUUUUCUAAUAAAGAUGGAACAGUU